AGAAGCGGCCGUGCCCAGCGCGCAGAGCGGAGCGCGCCGAAGCCUGAGCUCGUGAGGGGGCCGAGGCUGUGGGGAGGUGGCAGUUGGACUUCGGAAUCUCAAGGACUCCGACUCCUGGCUUGUUCAGAGAAGGAGAGCCCCGACUCCUGGAUCCCUGGGAGUCCCAGCGGCCAUGGGGACGCGAAGCAGCCCCGAGGAGGGGACCCCGCCGCCGCUGGUCCCGGAAUGCGACGUGGAGGUCCAGCCCCAGGGCCAUCCCGAGGAGUCCCGGGAACAGGAGGCAUCCGAAGUCCUGGCGGAACCUUCGAGCCGCGGGGGAGCUGAGCAGCAGGCAGAGGAAGAAGAAGUGGGAGAAGGCAGCAGCACUGAGAGCAGCCGCGACGCGCCCGAGGCUACGCCUCCGAUAGCUAUGGCGGCCACACCUCCCGCAUCCACCUCUUCGCGGGAAGGGGUGCGAGGGGCGGCGCGGCGCCUGCAAGGACAGCAGCUGGAGGCAUUGACUCGUGUGGCCCUGAUGGAGCAGCGAGUGAAGGAGCUACAGCGCCAGAGGAAGGAGCUGAGGAUCGAGAUGGAGGUGGAGGUGGCCUUGCUGCGGGGUGAGCUGGCUGGGGAGCGAGUGGCCGCUCGCCGGGAGGAGGAGCAGCUGCGGGAGCUGCUGGAGCAGCAGGCGGCCUCGGAGCAGCGCGGCCGCCAGCAGCGGGAACAGGAACAGAGGCGGCUGAGCCAGGAACGGGAUCGCCUAGAGGGUCUUCGCCAGAGACUCCGCAAGGCCCAGGGACAGCUCGACUCACAGCCAGAGGACCAACGCGAGCGGCUUCUGCAGGGUGUGCAGGAGAUGAGGGAACAACUGGAUGUGGCCCAACGUGCCUAUGAGGACCUGGAGUUCCAGCAACUGGAGCGGGAGAGCCGGCAGGAGGAGGAGGAUCGGGACAGCCCUGGGCCCCAGGUGCCAGACCCCAAGGUCCAGGAACUCCAGGCCAGCAUGGCGCAGCACAGAAGGGGUGCUCUGCAGCACCGGAUCCGGGUCCUGGAAGAGCAGCUCAAGUCACUGGGGGAGCAGAUGGCAGCCGAGAGCCGGGGGUUGAGCCGGAAGAAGGAGGAGGCCCUUCAGGCCCUGUCACAGGAACGGAGCCGGCUGCUCGAGCUCAAUUGCCUUCAGGGAACACCUGGCGGGGACUUCUCUGAGCCCAACCCGGCCCUCACUAAGCUGCUGUUCACCCAGAAGACAGACCGCCAGCUGCUGGUGCUCCAGGAUGCCGUGGCCCACUCCGCUGCCACCCCUACUUCUUCCUGCCUCUUUUCUGUCCACAGCUCCCUGCAGGGCUCCAUUGGCCUCCAGAGGACUGGGAGCCUGCCCCGGAAAAGGGGGGAGAGGGGGAGCCAGAGAGGAUCCCCCCGACCUCUGUCCUUCCAUUGUACUGAAUCCCUGGAGGCCUCAGCUCUCCCGCCAGCAGUGGGGGACUCCGGCAGAUACCCCCUCUACCAGCUGCUGAACUGUGGCCGUGGGAAUAGCUGUGGGGCCAUCCAUCCAGACAUUGCCCACAUGGAGCGGCUCCUGCAGCAGGCCAUGGCGGAGAGGGAGCGGCUGCUCAAGGCCCGGGAAGGAACAAGAAGGGGCACGGAAGGUUCCUCAGGCCCUGCUGUUCCUGCCAUCACGGCCCCACCCACCCCACCCCACCCUCCAGGCCCGCGAAUCUUGGAUCUCCGGCAGCAUCUGGAGGGAUGGGGCCACAACCCGGAAAACUGCCCACAUGUGCAGGUGUCUGGGUGCUGCUGCCGUGGACCCCUGGUGAAGAUGGGCGGCCGCAUCAAGACCUGGAGGAAGCGAUGGUUCUGCUUUGACCGCCAAGCCCGCCGCUUGGCCUACUAUGCGGACAAGGAAGAGACCAAGCUCAAAGGUGUCAUCUACUUCCAGGCCAUUGAGGAAGUCUAUUAUGACCACUUACGCUGUGCCUUCAAGAGCCCCAACCCCCGCCUGACCUUCUGCGUCAAAACCUACGAACGCCUUUUCUACAUGGUGGCUCCGAGCCCCGAAGCCAUGCGCAUUUGGAUGGACGUCAUCGUGACCGCCGCUGACGAAAACCACGCCCCCUGAGUGGCCCCGCCCUCUUGGGGGGAAGUCCCUUCGAGGCUCCGCCGGCGCGGGGCGCGGGGGCGUUCCUAGGCCCCGCCCACUGCCGGAAAACUUGGACGCACCGCUUUGGAACUCUCCCGGGAAUUCCGCAGGCGCGGCAGUUCAGCUGGCCUGAGCUGCUGCGUUCUGGGUUGCAGGUGCCUUGCCCCCGACGGGAUCGCCGGCCCCUAAGGCCCUGCCCGGGGCAGGAGGAAGAUUGCAGGGGCGGGAAGAAACUAUUUAUUGGUGCUCCUGUGAUACCGAAUUAAAUACGGAGGAAAAACAGGAA